AGUCAGCCCAGAAGCGGCUCAUUGAAAGCAGACCCUCUUCGGCGCUCGCUGGGCGGAGGACGCGCCGCGGUCCGCAGACCCGAGCGAGCUGGGCACCGCCGGGCGCCCCCGGCCCUGCCGCCCCCUCCUCCCCGCCGCUCCCCCGCGAGCCCGGCCAGGCGCGCCUGACGUGGACCAUUAAACUUGGAGCUGCCGCCUCGUCCCCUCUCCUCCUCCUCCUCCCUCUGACAGGCGAGCGAGCGACUCGGUGCAGGCAGGAGACGUGCUGCCGGGCUGGGCUGCCCGGGGGAGAUGACUCCUCGCCAGGAGGGCGCCUCUGGGAAGAAGACCACGGGGGAAGCAAAGUUUCAGGGCAGCUGAGGAGCCUUCGCCGCAGCCCUUCCGAGCCCAAUCAUCCCCCUGGCUAUGGAGGGCGGACUCUAAGAUGAAUCCCGACCUGGACACCGGCCACAACACAUCAGCACCUGCCCACUGGGGAGAGUUGAAAAAUGCCAACUUCACUGGCCCCAACCAGACCUCGAGCAACUCCACACUGCCCCAGCUGGACAUCACCAGGGCCAUCUCUGUGGGCCUGGUGCUGGGCGCCUUCAUCCUCUUUGCCAUCGUGGGCAACAUCCUAGUCAUCUUGUCUGUGGCCUGCAACCGGCACCUGCGGACGCCCACCAACUACUUCAUUGUCAACCUGGCCAUGGCCGACCUGCUGUUGAGCUUCACCGUCCUGCCCUUCUCAGCGGCCCUAGAGGUGCUCGGCUACUGGGUGCUGGGGCGGAUCUUCUGUGACAUCUGGGCAGCCGUGGAUGUCCUGUGCUGCACAGCGUCCAUUCUGAGCCUGUGCGCCAUCUCCAUCGAUCGCUACAUCGGGGUGCGCUACUCUCUGCAGUAUCCCACGCUGGUCACCCGGAGGAAGGCCAUCUUGGCGCUGCUCAGUGUCUGGGUCUUGUCCACCGUCAUCUCCAUCGGGCCUCUCCUUGGGUGGAAGGAGCCGGCACCCAACGAUGACAAGGAGUGCGGGGUCACCGAAGAACCCUUCUAUGCCCUCUUCUCCUCUCUGGGCUCCUUCUACAUCCCUCUGGCGGUCAUUCUAGUCAUGUACUGCCGUGUCUAUAUAGUGGCCAAGAGAACCACCAAGAACCUAGAGGCAGGAGUCAUGAAGGAGAUGUCCAACUCCAAGGAGCUGACCCUGAGGAUCCAUUCCAAGAACUUUCACGAGGACACCCUUAGCAGUACCAAGGCCAAGGGCCACAACCCCAGGAGUUCCAUAGCUGUCAAACUUUUUAAGUUCUCCAGGGAAAAGAAAGCAGCUAAGACGUUGGGCAUUGUGGUCGGUAUGUUCAUCUUGUGCUGGCUACCCUUCUUCAUCGCUCUACCGCUUGAGCUAUUUACCAGCACACCAAAGGGUCUGGAAAAGGACUGGAAAUAAUCUUGGAAGAAACUCUUUCCUCAAAGGACUCUGGAUCACUGAGAGGCCAAGCAGUGCUGCCUCUGGGACCUGGUGACAAAGCCUGAUCCUGCAUUGCGAAGAGGAGCAUUCUGCUUGGAACAAGGCACUGUGGGACCUGAAGGGAAGAGAGUUCCGUCUAGCCCUUGAGGCUUUGCAACUUUGGGAGGGCUGGGACAUAGCAUAGCCCUGAAGGAGAAGGAGAGCUCACAGAAGCACCAGAAGCAUCAGCAGCAGUGACUACUCUUUAAUGCAACUUGCUGAAAGCAGUUAUUAAGAAGGUGGUGGGAAGAAAGGAACCCACAGGGCCCCCAGAAAUAUCUAGGGAGCCUUUUUAAGAGGGCCUGAGUUUCACAGGUGAGGACUAAUAGACAGAUUUUCUUUUAAGAGACAAUGCUCACCCAGGCUGGUAUGCAGUGACACAGUCAUAGUUCACUGCAGCCUCGAACUCCUGGCUCAAGGGAUCCUCUCACCUCGGCCUCCCAAGUAGCUGGGACUACAGGUGCAUGCCACCAUGAUCUUCUAAUCUUUAAAAUUUGUAGAGACAGAGCCCCACUAUGUUGCCUAGGCAUAUCUCAAACUACUGGCCUCAAGUGAUCCUCCUGCCUUGGCCUCCCAAAGCACUGGGAUUACAGGUGUAAGCCAGUAUAUCCAACCUAGACAGAAAAUAUUGAUUAUUCACACUCACGUGACCUAAUUUGCACCCUCUGACUUGUGAGACUAGAGAGAGUCAUCUUGGAAAAGAGGUGUGUGCUCUGAGGCUGGCUCUUUUAUUUGAACCGACAGCUUUUAGUACCAAGAGCUGGAGCUGUGAUUCUCAAACUCAGAGAGGAGAAGAAUCACUCAGUGAGCUGAUUAAAAAUACCGACUCACAGUCACCUCCAGCCCCGUCUAACGGAUUUAGCAGAUAGAAAUAAGACCCAGUAAUCUGCGUUUUAAAGAAAUGAUACAGUUGGUCCAUGGACCAGAUAUUGAGAAGCAUUGCACAGAUGGUCAGUGACUCAGGAGGGCUCGAUUUACGAUCUAUCCACUUUACGAUGGGUUUUUGGAGACGUUAGCCCCAUCGUAAUUCCAGGGGCAUGGGUGAUCCAGCUUACAUUGCCGGGUAAGGGCUAGGUUUUACUCCCCCCUCAACGGCGCCUACUGUCUUAACAGGGUCCACUUUGCUAAACACCGAGUUGGAAAAGCAGCUUCCUCUCUUUCCCAAUCUCUGAUGGUGCUGCUUCCAGGUGUAACUUCUACCUGCCCUCUGCCUUAAGGGUCCCUAGAACCCAGGAUGGCUCCAGAGAAAGUAAGCUUGUCAUCGACCCGUCACUUCCCAGGUGGUUAACGUCCACACCCUGCCCCCAGCGGCGGGGGAGCCGGGCCUACGGGCUAAAGGACGGUGUUGUAAGAAGCUGGACGAGCCCGGUUCCAGAAACCAAACAGCAGUUGUUAUCAUGCCUUUUAAAUCACGCGUAGAGGUUUCAGUUUCUUCCUCUGCAGGCCCGUAAAUAUUUGCCUUCGGGUUUCUGUGUUUUCUGCCGUUGCCAGGAGCUCCGAUCCUCCUGCGGCGGGGGCGCCCAGGUGCGCGGGUCUCUCCUGCGGGCUCAGCGGGCCGGCGCCGCGGCGUCUCCAGCAGAGCGCAGCAAAGAAGACGAAGCCUCCUGGGGCCUUUCCUCGCCGCCUGGAGCGGGGCAUCCUUCCUCCUUACGUGCAGAGACUGGGAAGCAGCUCUUUAGACACUGCAGUGACCGAGCCCGCUCCACGCCCCUUUCCCCUGAGCAGGUGCUUGACGUGGGGCAAGCUCGGCGUUGAGGUGGACCCGCGCGCCACCCGCUGGCCAACGCGCCUAAGCGACAGGAGUGCAAAGAAACGAGGCUGCUUGGCAAUUCAGCUGGUGCGGCCCUGCGGCACUUCCCUUAUUCCUUCAUAGAUGCAGUCAGAUAUUCUAGAAUUCUAGGUUAGGAAUGCUUUAACCUGGGGUCCGUGCGCUGGCUUCAGGGAAUCUGGGAGCUCUCUAAAAUGCUAUAAACAAUGUAAUAUUUUUCUGGAAAAGGGGUGCACACUUUUCAUGAGUCUGACUAAUUUUAUAUGGUCUAUGGACCAAGUGCCAGGCAAUGUGCAAGCCAUUGGUGGUAAGUAGUGAUCAAGCAGACGUGUCGCUUCUCCUCGUGGACUUUGUAGUCUUUGUGGUAGGCUGAAGAAUGCCCCCCCUCGGCCGGCCGCCCAAAAUAUGUUCACAUCCUAAUCCCUGGAACCUGUGAAUGUUACCCGUUAUGGCAAAGGGGACUUUGCAGAUCUAAUCAAGUUAAGGAUCGUGAGAUGGGGGGAUUAGCCUGGAUUAUCCUGGUGGGCCUGAUAUCACAAGGGGUCUUAUAAGAGGAACACAAAAGGAAACAGACAGAAGACAAUGUGACAACAGAAGCAGGAGAACAAAGGGACGGACAUUUUAAGAUGCCACACUGCUGACUUUGAAGAUGGGAGACUUUGAAGAUGGGGAAAGGAGGCCGUGAGCCAAAGGAUGUGGGCAGACUCUGAAAGCUUGAAAGGUCAAGGAAACAGCUUCUCCCCAGGAGCCUCGGGAAAGAAUCCCACUGCUGACACCUUGACUUUAGCCCAGUAAAACUGACUGUAGACUUCUGACCUCCAGAACUGCAAGAGAAUCAAUAUGUUUGUUGCUUUAUGCCACUAUUUUGUAAUGCUUUGUUACAGCAGCUUUAGGAAGCUAAUAUGCAUCUCAGCAGGUGUCAGACUCUAAAAGUGGUAAGAGACCACAGUCCUUUACAAUGCUGAGAUUCUCUGUAUCACUGGCCCUUCCCCUCUCCAGGAGGAGACAACCAAGAGACAGAAAGUCCAACUGACACUACAGAAGUAGAUUUACUGAACUCACCCAUGCCAUAGAGGUACGUCUACACCUGAGUCUCUUUCCUAGAGAGUUUCAGAACUAGUUAGGGAGAUAAAAUUCAAAUUACAUCUGUGGCCGGGCAUGGUGGUGCAUGCCUGCAAUCCCAACAGUUUAGGAGGCUGAAUGGGAGGAUCACUUGAGCCCAGGAACUUGAGACCAGCCUGGACAACAUAGCAAGACCCCAUCUCUACAAAAAAAAUUUUAAAAAUUAGCCAGGUUUGGUGAUAUGCACCUAUAUUCCUAGCUACUCAGGAGACUAAAACAGGAGGAUUACUUGAGGCCAUACAUUGAUGGCCAUUUGGGCUGCUUUCUACCUUUUGGCUAUUGUGAAUAAUGCUGCUAUGAGGAUGGGCAUAUAAAUAUCUCUUCCAGACACUGCUUUCAAUUCUUUUGGAUAUAUGCCUAGAAAUGGAUUUUUUUGAGGAACUCCAAUACUGUUUUCCACAGUGGCUGCACAUUUUACAUUCCCACCAACAGUGCACAGGGGUUCCAAUUUUCACCACCUCUUCACCAACUUUGUUAUUUUUCUGGUGUUUGGUUUUUUUGUUUCUUUGUUUGUUUGUUUGUUUUUGAGAUGGAGUCU